CUACUACUCUAGGUGGUAGGAGUACAGCAAUAAACAGCACACAAAUGCUUGACCACAAGGCACUUCUAUUUCAGCAGGCUGGCCAUUAAAGAAUAAACAAAUAGCAACAGCAUUUAUACUAUAAUGUCAUAUAUAAUAUAAUGCUUAUAUAUUACAAGCAGAUAAAUUCUAUGAAGAAAUACAAAUGGUAUGAGGUAAUAGUAACGGUAUCGUGCUAUUUUGCAGCAUGUGUUCAUUGAAGGAUGAGCUUAGAAAAAAACAAGCAGAAAUCUGAACAGAGUGAAGGAGCAAGCUUUGCCAAUAUUCUGGUUGAAAAGAAAUAAAUGAUUUGACAAAGAAAAUAAUUGCUAAUGCUUCAAUUAUAACACUACUAUAUAUCUGAGGGUUGGUGUUUUCGAAGCAAAUAACACUAGUUUUUUUUUUCUUUCUUUUUUAAUUUUUUUAAACAGAGAAUCAUUCCAUACUCUCUGUAUGAUAAGCAGGCUGUUGGCAUAAGAAAAAGCAGAGCUCCUGGAUUCAGAAGACUUGAAUUCAGUAAUAUGUACUGUCUUUUACUAGCUGUUUGGUUCCAGGUAACUCAUGCCACCUAAUUUAAAAUGUAACAAUUGAGAGACUAUAAUAAAUGCCAGCUGUUUUGUAUCAGGCAUACCAUACUGUGUAUUUACAACCUGGAGAUAGGAAUUAUCAUCCCCAUUCAGAGAUGAUUAUAUGCUCCCUCAACAUUUUCUUUUCUUUGUGUCUUCCAGGCUUCAUGUGAAAGCACUUUGUACACAGUAAGUUGCUACCCAGUGUCAGCUAUUAUGCAUGGUACAGGACCAUACUUCUCAACUACAGUGUGUACACCCCUGGGACAUGAAGCCACCAAAUCAAUUGUCUGCAUUUUCUUUGGGUAUACAUUUUACCCUAUAGCAAAUACUUUAAAAUAUGUUUUAAGUAAACAGAUAUCAUGGAGUAAAAUGUAAAUUUUAUAUUUAUGUGAUAAAAGGUGUCUUAAUUUUCUUAUAUAUAAAUUGUUAUUGAUAUGUGAAUGUUAGCACGUAAUAGGGUUGUAGGAGGGUUGCAUUCUUAUAGAUAAGUAGGGAAACAUGCUGAGUUGACUGUGUUUAGCAUAUAAUAGAUGCUCAGGAAAUGCAAAUUUCCUUCUUUUCUUUCACUGGUAAGACAGGGGCGUUCAUGUAGUUUAAUCAUUUUAAGUAUUUGAAAUGUGUUCCUUAUUUUGAAAAUGUCCCUUAAAAUACUUUAUAAAUACUUUCAAUUUUUGCUUAUAAAUUCUACAUGUAUAAAUAGGGUUUCUCUAGCUAUCACCUGUCUAUAGGAAAAAAUAAUAAGUUCAUAUUAAAAGUAAUAACUCAGAAUUCAUUAACAUUGUCUCUAUCAAUGGGAGCCUCCCCUAAAAGUCACAGUUGGUUAUCUUCAGCUCAUAAACAUCCUUUCUUGUUCUUGGCUCAAGUCCUCUACCAUAUAGGUUGCUACUUUUAAAGUAAAAUUACUAAAUACUGGUAAUUUUGAGCACCUGUUCAUAUGUGUGUUGGACAUUUGAGUAACGUGGUUAUUCAUACCUAUUGUCCAUUUUUCACAUGGGCUGUACAAAUGGGACAAUAUGUAGUUCUACACACAUUCUGAAUUAUAUACAUUGCCUAUGUUUUCUUUCAGGAUUUGGAAGUAUUAUGUUUAAUUUUUCUUUUUUAUAAAGAAAUUUAGAGUUUACAUGCAAUCAAAUUUAAUAAACUUUCCCUUCCUGACUUGCACCUUUUGUGCUUAAGACACCUUCCCCUACCUCAACAUAUUGAGAUUAUCCUGUUUUCUUCUAAUGGGUUACUGGUCACAUUAGGUCUUCAAUGUGCUACACACUUUAAAUAAUCAGAUCUCUGUGACUCAGAGGAGAACUCACUCAUCAACCAGGGGAUGGCACUGAGCCAUUCAUGAGGGAUCCACCCCCAUGAGCCAAGCACUUCCCGUCAAGCCCCACCUCCAACACUGGGAAUCACAUUUCAGCAUGAGAUUUGGGGAAAAUAAAUAUCCAAACCAUAUGAUUCCAAAAACAUGAUCCAUGAAAGAAGAAAUUGAAAAAUUGAGCUUUAUCUACUGUAUACAUGUCAAAAAAUUUAAAUUGCACAUGUGAAAUAUGUGCAUUGUGUUGUAUGUCAGUUAUGCCUGAAUAACUCUGUUUUAAAAAUAACAGGAAAAUGGAUCCCAUUUUCUAAGAAUUCUGGAGGUGGUUGUAUACCCUCUGAAGAUGUCUUUCCCAGGAAGAAGGACUAUCUUGCUUAAAAAGUUAUUUCUUAUAUUUCACCAAAAUCUCUUUUACUGUACUGUAAACAUUUUAUUUUCCCUUUAAAAAAUAGUAACAGCUCACCUUGCUUCAUUUUGAAUGUUGAAUCACUUUUGGUGGUAUAAUCUUACAUAGUUUGGAUCCCUUAUAAGCUGAAAAGUCGUGAGAUGGAGAGUAAAUAUAAGGAGAUACUCUUGCUAACCAGCCUGGAUAACAUCACCGAUGAGGAACUGGAUAGGUUUAAGUGCUUUCUUCCAGAUGAGUUUAAUAUUGCCACAGGCAAACUGCAUACUCUAAACAGCACGAGUAGCCAACUUGAUUUAAAACGCUGGCAUGGUGUCUGCAGUGAGGAAGACCGUAUUUUUCAGAAGCUGAAUUAUAUGCUUGUGGCAAAAUGUCUUCGGGAAGAGCAGGAAACAGGUAUAUGUGGGAGUCCCUCAUCUGCCCGGUCCGUUUCUCAGUCAAGACUUGGUCUUUCCUUUCAUGGCAUUUCUGGGAAUGCAUGUUGA